AUAUUUUUCCCAGACGCGGAGGUUGGGGUCAUGGCGCCCCGAAGCCUCCUCCUGCUGCUCUCAGGGGCCCUGGCCCUGACCGAUACUUGGGCGGGCUCCCACUCCUUGAGGUAUUUCAGCACCGCUGUGUCGCGGCCCGGCCGCGGGGAGCCCCGCUACAUCGCCGUGGAGUACGUAGACGACACGCAAUUCCUGCGGUUCGACAGCGACGCCGCGAUUCCGAGGAUGGAGCCGCGGGAGCCGUGGGUGGAGCAAGAGGGGCCGCAGUAUUGGGAGUGGACCACAGGGUACGCCAAGGCCAACGCACAGACUGACCGAGUGGCCCUGAGGAACCUGCUCCGCCGCUACAACCAGAGCGAGGCUGGGUCUCACACCCUCCAGGGAAUGAAUGGCUGCGACAUGGGGCCCGACGGACGCCUCCUCCGCGGGUAUCACCAGCACGCGUACGACGGCAAGGAUUACAUCUCCCUGAACGAGGACCUGCGCUCCUGGACCGCGGCGGACACCGUGGCUCAGAUCACCCAGCGCUUCUAUGAGGCAGAGGAAUAUGCAGAGGAGUUCAGGACCUACCUGGAGGGCGAGUGCCUGGAGUUGCUCCGCAGAUACUUGGAGAAUGGGAAGGAGACGCUACAGCGCGCAGAUCCUCCAAAGGCACACGUUGCCCACCACCCCAUCUCUGACCAUGAGGCCACCCUGAGGUGCUGGGCCCUGGGCUUCUACCCUGCGGAGAUCACGCUGACCUGGCAGCGGGAUGGGGAGGAACAGACCCAGGACACAGAGCUUGUGGAGACCAGGCCUGCAGGGGAUGGAACCUUCCAGAAGUGGGCCGCUGUGGUGGUGCCUUCUGGAGAGGAACAGAGAUACACAUGCCAUGUGCAGCACGAGGGGCUGCCCCAGCCCCUCAUCCUGAGAUGGGAGCAGUCUCCCCAGCCCACCAUCCCCAUCGUGGGCAUCGUUGCUGGCCUUGUUGUCCUUGGAGCUGUGGUCACUGGAGCUGUGGUCGCUGCUGUGAUGUGGAGGAAGAAGAGCUCAGAUAGAAACAGAGGGAGCUACUCUCAGGCUGCAGCCUACUCAGUGGUCAGCGGAAACUUGAUGAUAACAUGGUGGUCAAGCUUAUUUCUCCUGGGGGUGCUCUUCCAAGGAUAUUUGGGCUGCCUCCGGAGUCACAGUGUCUUGGGCCGCCGGAAGGAAAGUUGACUCAUACUGGUGUCCAGUGAAGAAACCCAGGCGCAUAAGAGGGACAGUUGGAUCUCAGGUUUGUGCUUGAUCUGGAAAAGGAAGAGCAGAGACCACUAGGAGGCACCACUGCACUGCUCAUGAGCCCAGGAGGUGGAUGCCGGGGCUGAGCUCAGGGUGGAGAGAUGUCAUUGCUCAUCCUCCAGGUUCCAGGUGAAAACCCACCUGCCCAGCCCAUCUGGUUCUCCCUGGUUCUUCAAUUCUAGGGAGGACUGUCUUCUUCUCACCUCCCCGGACGAUGCUUCUUGACACAGGAAAGAGGAUGUGCUGCUAGGGUCAUCAUGUCCUGGUUUAUUGUGUUGUCAGUAGAAUGAAAUCAAAAUACAUACUUCAUAAAUAAUAAAAUAACCCAUAAUAAGUAAACAUUUACAAUUUACUCACACCAUUGAGGUUUCCUCCAGGUGUGAGCACAGCUGCAGACACACCUUGUCGCUUCAGUCAGGACACAGGACAGAGUAAAAUGGGAAGAAACCACAGUCACUGCAGAAAGGGCCCCCAUGGAAGAGGCCUGGCAGGGAGGCCAGCUGCCCCAGGGCCACCAUAUUUAGAGAUGACUUCCCCUUUCUAGGCAGGACUGGGAUUUUAAAAUUCUUUUUGUAUUCAUAGUUGUUCUGAAAUUGCAGGAUGAUGAGACCCAGCACUGGUGAGUUAUACUGUCUCUUUCUUCCCUAUUAAAUUCUGUGCCAAACAGCACCUUCAUAUAUUUAUCUCCUCUUCCUGGAGAGAAUAAAAACAAUGGAAAAAUUGAACCAUACAAACAUACUUUAAAUAUGUGCUGUCAGAAGUAGCUACUAAAGGAUUAAUUCCACCAAAGUGAGGGAAGGUUUGAAAAGAAAAACAUUGUAUUCCCAUAUUCAAAGCAGCAUUAUUCACGAUAGCCAAGACAACACACACCAACACAUGAAUGAAGAAAAUGUGGUAUAUAUCGACAACGGAAUAUCACUCAGCCUUAAAAAGGAAACCUGGUCACAGGCUGCAACAGGGAUGAACCUGAAGGACACUGCUAAGUAAAAUAAGCCAAUCACAAAGAAAACCCAAUACUGCACAUUUCCAUUUAUAUGAGGUGUCUAAACUGAAAGUAGACUAAUGGCUGCUAGGGGCUCGGUGAGGGGGAUGGAUGAAUGUUUGUUCAAUGGGCAUAGAGUUUCAGUGUUGCAAGAUGAAAAGUUCUAGAGAUCUGUUGCACAACUAUGUAUUUACAGUUAAUACUGUACUACUGUAUACUUUAAAAUAGUUAAGAUACCAAAUUUUACAUAAUGUAGUUUUUGGCCCAAGGAAAAGACUAAUUAGCCCUGUUACUAAUUUAGGGAAAAAGUACAUUAAUUCAUUAAAAAUAUAUUAGUAUGCGCUUACCUUAGAUACAGAAAACUAUGAGACAAAAAGAGAGAUCCCUGCUACCCCAGCUAUCACCCAUGAACCAGGAAAAUCAGCACCUCCUGAAACUAGACAGAAAGGCUCACAGGCCCAGCCUUGACAUGUUGAAUCAGUCUGCAUUUUGGCUGGAACCCAGGUGGCUCCACUGCAUGUAAAGCACCUUCCCAGAUAGUGAUGGAGGGAGAUCCUAGGACAGUGACUCUGCUCCACGGGGAGAAGCCUCCAGUCCAGAUGGGAGCAGCCAGAAGGGCCCAGGAGGGACAUUUCCAAGAAGAUAAAAUUAACAGAAUGUCCAAAGUGUCCAACGUCUUGAAAGAAUCAUACAAACAAAAGAGAUAUCGAACUUAAAUUAAUGAGAGUUAAUAAAAUAAACAAAAACAAAUGCAAGUAUUAACUCCAAGAAGAACCAAUGUUGUACAGGCAGUGAAAAGUAGUCCAGUUGACAUAUGAGAGGAUUAGUCAUGGUAAAAGAAACAAGAGAUGGCUGAACUAAACAUAAUCACUAUAUAAAUAUACUGGGAAGAGUGAAAGAGAACAAGUACUCUUAACUGUUGCAUCCACCAUUGCGCUGUGCAACAAUGGGUGCAUCUGAAAAAAAUCAAGCAAUAAUAAUAAAGAAAUGGUAGAGAUACAGAAGUAAAGUCAAAAGAAUCAGCUAAAAAACUUGAAAGUGGUUGGCCCCUAGAAAGGCAGAAAUUGAGAAGAGGCAGAGAGGACUCUCAUUUUUCUCAAGAGAUUCUGCACAAAUAUUUGACUCUUUCAAUUGUGCACAAUUAUAAAUUUGAUUAAAAUAAAAACAAAAGCUUCAGUGAAUAUGCAAGUUUAUGUCUAAUGACAACCGCAUUCAACAAUGAUAUUUAAGGGUUAACUAAAAUGUGAAAAUACUUAAACAUGAAACAGGCAUGUAUAAAUGUGUUUUUGACACCAAACGUGAACACAAAUGUGAAAUAAUACACCUGUAAACACAUCUCUGGAUAGAUAGCCCACGAUUGAAUUCUCUACCCCACCUCCUUUACUGGUUGACCUGUGAACACAGGCAGGCAGUGGACCAGGACCCAACUAGGUUCCUUCAUCCUCUUGCUUCUAGGCAGGCCUUGCAUCCACUUUUGCUGCACAGAGGGCUCCCAUCCCUGCCUUGGUCCGUUUCACAGGUGAUCCCCUAACUCUCCCUGCCACCACUGCCUUACCUGAGUGGAGCUGAGGCUACCCUGACCAAGAAGAGCACCACCCAUCUGUGCCCCAAGGCCAGAAAGUUAAAAGGAACCUCACAACAGGGUCAGGAACUAUCCCACCUCCCCACCUACCAAUCAGUCUGAACUGAUAAUGGGAGAUGCUGAUACUUGCUUUACUCAUCCUCAUUCCCAGUUCAUUUAUUCUUCAUUAAUUCAGUCCAAUCUCCCCAGUGGUCACUUAACCCCAGAAGCAGACUGAUCUCUAUUCUUCUUAAUCAGGAAAGUCCAAAGCACUCCCUGUCCUCUCCCUCAUAUCAGACUUCAGCUCUGCAUCUGCAAGAUGCAGAGGUCCUCUGCAAGGCAGGUGUCUUCCCACAGGGUCAGCCCCUAAACACUGGCUGCAGAUGUCCCCUCCAUCCCUUCCCAGCCCUUUCUGUGUUGCUGUGAAUCUGUCCAUCACCGAGAACUGGUGGGGAGAUGUGGGGGAGGUGGGGAGAUUUCUUUGUGCUGUGUCAAGGCAUCAAGACAGACCUCUCCUUCUCUCUUGAACCUCAUACUCUAUCCCUUCCCAGACACUUGAAAUAAAACACAGACCAGAAAUGUCUA